GAAGCAGCUGAAGCGGCGGUAGCGGCGGCGGCUCGGGCAGAGGGGCGGGAGCUGAGGCGGGAGCGGACAGGCUGGUGGGCGAGCGAGAGGCGGCGGAAUGGUGGACUACCACGCGGCGAACCAGUCGUACCAGUACGGCCCCAGCAGCGCGGGCAAUGGCGCUGGCGGCGGGGGCAGCAUGGGCGACUACAUGGCCCAGGAGGACGACUGGGACCGGGACCUGCUGCUGGACCCGGCCUGGGAGAAGCAGCAGCGCAAGACCUUCACGGCAUGGUGCAACUCCCACCUGCGGAAGGCAGGCACACAGAUCGAGAACAUUGAUGAGGACUUCCGAGACGGGCUCAAGCUCAUGCUGCUCCUGGAGGUCAUAUCAGGGGAGCGGUUACCUAAGCCGGAGCGGGGGAAGAUGAGAGUGCACAAAAUCAACAAUGUGAACAAAGCGCUGGACUUUAUUGCCAGCAAAGGCGUCAAGCUGGUCUCCAUCGGGGCAGAAGAGAUUGUGGACGGCAACGCAAAGAUGACCCUGGGAAUGAUCUGGACCAUCAUCCUUAGGUUCGCCAUCCAGGACAUCUCCGUGGAAGAGACCUCGGCCAAGGAAGGGCUCCUUCUCUGGUGCCAGAGAAAGACAGCCCCGUAUAAGAACGUCAAUGUGCAGAACUUCCACAUCAGCUGGAAGGAUGGUCUUGCCUUCAAUGCCCUGAUCCACCGGCACAGACCAGAGCUGAUUGAGUAUGACAAGCUGAGGAAGGACGACCCUGUCACCAACCUGAACAAUGCCUUCGAAGUGGCUGAGAAAUACCUCGACAUCCCCAAGAUGCUGGAUGCAGAGGACAUCGUGAACACGGCCCGGCCCGACGAGAAGGCCAUAAUGACCUAUGUGUCCAGCUUCUACCAUGCCUUUUCAGGAGCGCAGAAGGCUGAAACUGCCGCCAACCGGAUCUGUAAGGUGCUGGCUGUCAACCAAGAGAACGAGCACCUGAUGGAGGACUACGAGAAGCUGGCCAGCGACCUCCUGGAGUGGAUCCGGCGCACCAUCCCCUGGCUGGAGGACCGUGUGCCCCAAAAGACUAUCCAGGAGAUGCAGCAGAAGCUGGAGGACUUCCGCGACUACCGGCGUGUGCACAAGCCGCCCAAGGUGCAGGAGAAGUGCCAGCUGGAGAUCAACUUCAACACGCUGCAGACCAAGCUGCGCCUCAGCAACCGGCCCGCCUUCAUGCCCUCCGAGGGCAAGAUGGUCUCGGACAUCAACAAUGGCUGGCAGCACUUGGAGCAGGCUGAGAAGGGCUACGAGGAGUGGCUGCUGAAUGAGAUCCGCAGGCUGGAGCGGCUCGACCACCUGGCAGAGAAGUUCCGGCAGAAGGCCUCCAUCCACGAGGCCUGGACUGACGGGAAGGAAGCCAUGCUGAAGCACCGGGACUACGAGACGGCCACACUAUCGGACAUCAAAGCCCUCAUUCGCAAGCACGAGGCCUUCGAGAGCGACCUGGCUGCGCACCAGGACCGCGUGGAGCAGAUCGCCGCCAUUGCCCAGGAGCUCAACGAGCUGGAUUACUACGACUCCCACAAUGUCAACACCCGGUGCCAGAAGAUCUGUGACCAGUGGGACGCCCUCGGCUCUCUGACACAUAGUCGCAGGGAAGCCCUGGAGAAAACAGAGAAGCAGCUGGAGGCCAUCGACCAGCUGCACCUGGAAUACGCCAAGCGCGCGGCCCCCUUCAACAACUGGAUGGAGAGCGCCAUGGAGGACCUCCAGGACAUGUUCAUCGUCCAUACCAUCGAGGAGAUUGAGGGCCUGAUCUCAGCCCAUGACCAGUUCAAGUCCACCCUGCCGGACGCCGAUAGGGAGCGCGAGGCCAUCCUGGCCAUCCACAAGGAGGCCCAGAGGAUCGCUGAGAGCAACCACAUCAAGCUGUCGGGCAGCAACCCCUACACCACCGUCACCCCGCAAAUCAUCAACUCCAAGUGGGAGAAGGUGCAGCAGCUGGUGCCAAAACGGGACCAUGCCCUCCUGGAGGAGCAGAGCAAGCAGCAGUCCAACGAGCACCUGCGCCGCCAGUUCGCCAGCCAGGCCAAUGUUGUGGGGCCCUGGAUCCAGACCAAGAUGGAGGAGAUCGGGCGCAUCUCCAUUGAGAUGAACGGGACCCUGGAGGACCAGCUGAGCCACCUGAAGCAGUAUGAACGCAGCAUCGUGGACUACAAGCCCAACCUGGACCUGCUGGAGCAGCAGCACCAGCUCAUCCAGGAGGCCCUCAUCUUCGACAACAAGCACACCAACUAUACCAUGGAGCACAUCCGCGUGGGCUGGGAGCAGCUGCUCACCACCAUUGCCCGCACCAUCAACGAGGUGGAGAACCAGAUCCUCACCCGCGACGCCAAGGGCAUCAGCCAGGAGCAGAUGCAGGAGUUCCGGGCGUCCUUCAACCACUUCGACAAGGAUCAUGGCGGGGCGCUGGGGCCCGAGGAGUUCAAGGCCUGCCUCAUCAGCCUGGGCUACGACGUGGAGAACGACCGGCAGGGUGAGGCCGAGUUCAACCGCAUCAUGAGCCUGGUCGACCCCAACCAUAGCGGCCUUGUGACCUUCCAAGCCUUCAUCGACUUCAUGUCGCGGGAGACCACCGACACGGACACGGCUGACCAGGUCAUCGCUUCCUUCAAGGUCUUAGCAGGGGACAAGAACUUCAUCACAGCUGAGGAGCUGCGGAGAGAGCUGCCCCCCGACCAGGCCGAGUACUGCAUCGCCCGCAUGGCGCCAUACCAGGGCCCUGACGCCGUGCCCGGUGCCCUCGACUACAAGUCCUUCUCCACGGCCUUGUAUGGCGAGAGCGACCUGUGAGGCCCCAGAGACCUGACCCAACACCCCCGACGGCCUCCAGGAGGGGCCUGGGCAGCCCCACAGUCCCAUUCCUCCACUCUGUAUCUAUGCAAAGCACUCUCUGCAGUCCUCCGGGGUGGGUGGGUGGGCAGGGAGGGGCUGGGGCAGGCUCUCUCCUCUCUCUCUUUGUGGGUUGGCCAGGAGGUUCCCCCGACCAGGUUGGGGAGACUUGGGGCCAGCGCUUCUGGUCUGGUAAAUAUGUAUGAUGUGUUGUGCUUUUUUAACCAAGGAGGGGCCAGUGGAUUCCCACAGCACAACCGGUCCCUUCCAUGCCCUGGGAUGCCUCACCACACCCAGGUCUCUUCCUUUGCUCUGAGGUCCCUUCAAGGCCUCCCCAAUCCAGGCCAAAGCCCCAUGUGCCUUGUCCAGGAACUGCCUGGGCCAUGCGAGGGGCCAGCAGAGGGCGCCACCACCACCUGACGGCUGGGGACCCACCCAGCCCCUCUCCCCUCUCUGCUCCAGACUCACUUGCCAUUGCCAGGAGAUGGCCCCAACAAGCACCCCGCUUUUGCAGCAGAGGAGCUGAGUUGGCAGACCGGGCCCCCCUGAACCGCACCCCAUCCCACCAGCCCCGGCCUUGCUUUGUCUGGCCUCACGUGUCUCAGAUUUUCUAAGAACCAAAAAAAAAAAAGGAAAAAAAACACAAAACAACAAAAACCAAAAAAAAAAAAAAUCACAAAAACAAAAAAACUAUAAAAAAGAAAGAAUUAAAAACUUUCAGAGAAUUACUAUUUACUUUAUUAACUUACGGAUUUAUUAUAUAAAUAUAUAUUCACCUAGCAACAUAUCUCUGCCGUCUCUCCUGCUCUCAUAAUGAAGACAUAGCCGAUUCUCUGCCCGGGCCCCUUGCUGAUGCUCCUCCGGGUCUGCGUCGGGCGUGGGUCUCUGGGGACCCUCCAGAGGUGGAGGUGGGCUGAUGGCCUGGCUGCCUGGUGGUUGAUGGUUUUGCUCCCCCUACCUUUUUUUUUUGAGUUUAUUCUGAUUGAUUUUUUUUCUUGGUUUCUGGAUAAACCACCCUCUGGGGACAGGAUAAUAAAACAUGUAAUAUUUUUAAGAAGGAUUCCUGCAGCAUCAUCUUUUUUUAUUUCUCCUGUGUCUGUCCUCCACCUUCUAGGAGAGCCAGGGCAGAGCUAGCACUGUCUUAAGCUGUCAACGUGGACUAGCUCGUGUCAUCUGCUCGAGAAGGGCUGUCGCUGUUCUUGUUUCUGAGUGAGGAGUACGCAGGCCAGAGUGGUCACCCGGCCGUGAGCAGUGAGGGCCAGAGACUAGCCCCAGACAGGUGGAUGCCAGAGAGAGUGGCACCCAUGCCAGGCAAGGCCUAGGGAGGUGGUCUUGCUCAGCAACCCUGCCCUGAGCAGCAGGUGCGCCCAUCCGGAGAUCCUAGGAGAAGGUGGCCACCUCCAUCCACUAAGGAAGAGAAGGAAGACAGUGGCUUGAGGCAGGGAGCUCGCAGGACAGAGCCUGAGCCACCCUGUCCCUCCCACCUGGCUCACCUGUCUGUGGGUCAGGCAGAUGACCCCCUCACCCCCAUCCAGGUGCUGGCUGCAGUGGCCUGUGCAGAGAGGGGCAGGGUGAGUGCCCACCAGUCCCCGUACCCCUUCCCCCCAUGCCCCACCAUGCCGGGGUGGUACUCACAGAAGAUGCAGGUGAGGUGGGCCACACAGGACACGAACCGCUCGAAGUCCACACGCAGACGGCUAUCCCGGUAGCGGCUGGUGAGGGUCUGGGUCAGCUGGUUGUUCAGGUGGAAGCCUAGGGGGAGGCUGCUUCUGAGCCCAGUGGCCCACAGGGAACCCACCUUGGCAUUGCAUCCCCACCCCACCUCCUCAGGGAGGACAUGAAUGCCACAGGGUGUCACACCCCAACUCUGCCCCAUCCCGGCAGGGUGAGUACAGGCUGAUCCCUUCAAUCCUCUGGGCCUGUUUCCUCAUCCAUCAAACGGACUAAGACAGCCCCGACCCCAUAGGGUGUGUGAAGACAGAACGCUCAGGACAGCGUCUGACACGUGACUCGAUGUGUGGGUACUGUUACUCCUUAAAUCCUGUGGGGCUUUCUCCUUGCCAGUGGGCACUGGAGGAUAUUUCUGUGCAGCAAAAAAUAUAGUCAAUCCCAUAUGGA